CUGCCUGGCCGGGGCCGCACUGCGCCGCCCGCCGCCCGCCGCCCGCCGCCCGCCGCCGGCGACGGCACCGCCGCCCUGCGAUCCGGCCGCGGCGGCUCAGAGCGCGGCUGCGGCGGGCGCGGGCGGCGGUGGCUCCCUCCCGUGCGUCCGUCGUGGGACCUUUGCCCGCUCGCCCGCGGGGGACAGCGCGCGCUCCGGUCCGCGGCAGGGGCGGGGACGCCCGGCCUGUGGCCCCCGCGCCCCCCAUGUUCUAGGCCUGGCUCUGCCGUGGCUUGCUGACCUUGGAGAAUUGGAGAAGCUUGUGCCCUGCUGGAAAGUGGGAUGGCAGUACCCGCUUCAUCUAGUAGUCGGGGAGAUCAAGAGAGGUAUGGGACCUGAAGAGGAUGGCAGACUGUGCAGUGCGGUGCACACCGGUCUCCAGGUUGUUUUCACCCUCCUAUCUCCUCCCAGGAGCUAACGUAUAAAGCUGAGGCUCGGCCAGGGACUGUGAUAUACCCACAUCCCCGGAACUAGGUGAUCGCGGUGCAGGAACCAGGUGUGCCUUCGCGGGAUCCAUGCCUUGAGGCCCAGGAACGCCCCGCCGCCAGCAUGCCGUGGGACGCGCGGCGGCCUGGGGGUGGCGCGGACGGCGGGCCCGAGGCCUCGGGCGCGGCGCGCUCGCGAGCGCAGAAGCAGUGCCGCAAGUCGUCGUUCGCCUUCUACCAGGCGGUGCGCGACCUGCUACCCGUGUGGCUGCUGGAGGAUAUGCGCGCCAGCGAGGCCUUCCACUGGGACGAGCGCGGGCGCGCCGCCGCCUACUCGCCCUCUGAGGCGCUGCUCUACGCGCUCGUGCACGACCACCAAGCGUACGCGCAUUACCUGCUGGCCACGUUCCCGCGGCGCGCGCUCGCACCGCCCAGUGCCGGCUUCCGCUGCUGCGCGGCUCCCGGGCCGCACGUGGCGCUGGCAGUGCGCUACAACCGCGUGGGCAUUCUGCGCCGCAUCCUGCGCACCUUGCGCGACUUCCCGGCCGAGGAGCGGGCGCGCGUGCUGGACCGGCGUGGCUGCAGCCGCGUGGAGGGCGGUGGCACGUCGCUGCACGUGGCCUGUGAGCUGGCGCGCCCCGAGUGCCUCUUCCUGCUGCUGGGCCACGGCGCCUCGCCCGGUCUGCGGGACGGCGGCGGCCUCACGCCUCUCGAGCUGCUGCUGCGCCAGCUGGGCCGCGACGCCGGGGCCACUCCCUCCGCCGCCGGAGCCCCCGCCUCAGCUCCCGGGGAGCCGCGCCAGCGCCGCCUGCUGCUGCUGGACCUCCUGGCGCUGUACACCCCCGUGGGUGCCGCCGGCUCGGCCCGCCAGGAGCUGCUGGGCGACCGGCCGCGCUGGCAGCGGCUGCUGGGUGAGGACAAGUUCCAGUGGCUGGCGGGCCUGGCGCCGCCCUCGCUCUUCGCGCGCGCCAUGCAGGUGCUGGUCACCGCCAUCUCUCCAGGCCGCUUCCCCGAGGCCCUGGACGAGCUGCCGCUGCCCCCAUUCCUGCAGCCGUUGGACCUCACUGGCAAAGGCUAGGCCCGGAGCACCCUAGGCGCUGGAUUUUGGGACAAAACUAUUUUUCAGAGCGUUGUACCGGCACUUUAUAUAUAUUGAUCUCUGUACGGCACAAUCUCUGCCUCAUCUGUCGCAUGCACUGGGGGCUGGGCUUGGAUGGUCAGGUGAGUUCCAAGUGGCAGGUUUUCUGGGUGCAGCUGGGCUCGGGCCUUCAGCUCGCUGUCCAGCCCCUGAAGGGAGUGAGGACUAACCUCCCACCUUGAUCUAGAGCCUCGGACAGGUGUGCGUCCCAGAUGGGUGACAGCUGAGUGCCGCAGGAGCUCGGUAGGUGCAGGGGUGGGGACUGGCAUGUCCAAGCAGCAGGACAGCGUAUAAAAAGGCCUGGAAGCCAAGAGAACGAGCUCUGCAGCGUAGGGUUCUCACGGGAGGUCCUGUGCGGUCAGCCUUUUGCACCCUGUGGACUCCGGGCCAGGGAGGGCACACAGGGCUGGCAGGCCCGCGGUGGCUGGUGUUGAGGCAUGAACAAAUUGUACCGGGUAUCCCCCACCCCACUCUGACCACCAGUUCCUCCUUGGAUAUCACUCCCCCUGACAGGCAGCCCACCCAGGCCUGGAUUUGUCCCUGUCUCCCCCUUUUGCUUUUCCCCCAUGACUAAUGGGCACCAGGUCUUGCUGCUCCUGCUUCUCACCUCUGCAGUGGCAGCAGGCCCCUGGCCCCAGGUGCAUGCCGGUCAGUGGGGUUGGAUGUGCCUUCCUCCAGGCCUGCCCUCUGUCCAAGCCCGGAGUGGGCUUGGUGGGCUCCCUGGUGGCCCCCAGUGGGUGCCAGGUGGUGCCCGGGGUUAUUGAGGGGUGGUUGUAUCACUGUAGGGACAGGCUUCUUGCCCCAGCCUGGAGAGCUGUUUUCUUCAGGAAGGUUCUGGAGAUGGAGACUUGUUUGCGAAUUCACCACAACUCCAGGCUGGGAGGCUGGGUCUCCGCUCUCAGAGCCGAGACACCAGGGAGGAUAGCCAGGCUGCCCUGCCUGGGAAUUCUGCUGGGCCGUCAAAUUCAACCCGCACCAACGUGGGCAGGAGGGCCACAGUGUCCUGCCAGGAGCAGAGGGCUGAAGGUCUGCAGGAGGAAGAACCACUAUCCUGGUGGGGGGCACCUGCUGCCCACCCUGCCCCCAGCGUGCCUGGGGGGAGCACACCUGGGCAUGGAGGAGUCCAGGGUGCUGGGCCACACAAGAGAGGUGGGGGAGAGGCCUGGACAGUAGGAAGAUCUUGCCCAGGGUCCUGGAUCCGCCACUCUGGGGGUGACCUUGGACAAACCUCUGCCUUGGCCCUCAGUCUCCCCAUCAAGGUUUUUCCAUUCAGGAGGUUUUGGGCCAUCUUCAGCCACCCUACCAGCCCUGAAAAGGAUGUGACUCCUGUUUCUGGGAAGUGUGUGGUGUGUUAGGUGGGCCUACAGCCCUGGUUGUGGGGAGGGAAGGAUGGAGAGACAGCACAGUGACAGAGCCCAGACUGCAGGCUGGAGUGAGGGUUCCACUUCCCCGCUGCUGUGUGUCCUGGACCAGUGCCUCUGAACCUUGGCACUUGGGGCAGUGGAUAUUAACAUCUUUCCAAGCCCAAUUCUUGGGGCAUCAGGGCCUCCGGUCCUCUGGGAGGUGGCAGGUCCUCAGAUUGGAGAUGCCAUGGGGGGGGGAGGUGCCUCUCCUUUGGAGGGUAUGGAAGUGGAGACAGGAGUGGCCUGGCGCAGCUGCCGUGGUUCUUAGGGGCUGGGCCCGGGGAGCCCAUGGGGCUUGUGCCUAGAAAGCCUGGGCUCCUCACUGGGGUCUAGAUGUGCAGACUUCAUGUCUCCCCAGCUCCAGCUCUGUUCUCUAUAGGUCAGCCUCCACAAUGCCAGAGGCCCAGGGCUAGCCCCCUCCACGUCCCUCCUAGAUCUACAGCUGCCCCUUUGAUGACAGCGCCAUUGAGUCCCCUGGGCUGGGGGGGUCAUGCAGGGGUGAGGCAGCUGCCUGCCGCCGGUACUCAUUGCCUGGCCAGGCAGGACACAGGCUGGCGGGCACUGAGAGUGGGCCCCACGAAAUCCAUUGUCAGGUUACCAGGAUGAAGAACCCAGGCUGGUCGUGGAGUGCAGGGCGGGGCCUGCCGGAAGAAUUAUGGGCACUGCAGCAGGAGGGCAGCCUGGGCCAUUAGCUCCUGAUGUCAUCGAUUUGGGUGAGGGGACAGGGAAGUCAGAGGAAGCUGGCCAGUGGCUCUCACGAAGACUUACAGCAGCGGAGUGGUGCCUGAUUCCUAGUACAGCUGCUCCCACUGAGUCUCCAGGGAUCUGUGGUUCAGGACCCCCUGCAACCCCCUCCCAGACCCCUGUACUGGUGGGAGGAGAGGACCUAGAGGAAAGGUGCUGGGCAGAUAAGCAGCCGAGGGAGGCCCUGGGUUUAGCUUAUCAGUCUUCUGGGCCCUCCUGCCCCAGGAAGGGCAGCGAGGACCAUGGUGUUGCCCCUGUCAUCGUUAUCGUCCUGGCCAUGAGCUUGCAGGACUGGGAGGGCCGGAGUCAGCCAGGCAGACGGCAGCACAGCAUUUGCCUGUUGGCAGGUGGCCUUGGUGGCUUCCCAAAGGCAAUCGCUCCACGCAGAACAAAACUCACUUUUUUGGGGGGUGAAGCACCUUGGUUCAUUUGUUUAGUUCGUUAAUUCCAGCAGUCUGUUUCUAAGGGAAACAUGGCUGCAGCCGGUCCUGCCCCUCCACCCACCCACCAGGUGCCCAGUGUUCCCAAGGGCCCCGAAUCCCAACCUUAUUCAGGCGUCAGCAUCUCUGCACCCCAAAUGCCUGUUAGGGAGGAUAGUGAAGGCUGAGCCCUCCUGGGCUCAUCAAAAGCCAGCAGUGAGAGAACACCCCCAUCUCUCUGAGGUGACCUUGUAGGGCAGUCCGUGCUGUCUGGCUGGCCUGGGUGAGGUGGGCAGGGACCAAGGCCUGGCGCCUGGGCCUCGCUGGCCUUGCUCUGCGUGCUGACUUCAUCCUGAUAGUACCUUGAUUUUCCUACUGUGACUUCCCCUUCUGUCGACUUCCUCACCAACUUUAAAAUUCCGUAUUGAGAGCAGUUUCCUAAGUUACCUCAAAUCCUAUUCAGAAGAAGGUUCUUCCUGGAAGUUGGGAGGGCGGAAAACAAGUUUAGUCACAGAAGACUACUCCAUGUUUGAGCUUCUGUUUCAAGGGAAGUGAGUAACUGCCGGAGGAGCCCUGCCCCUCUGCAGUGUGUGGUGUUGCCCUGAUACUUUUCAGAUUGAGGUGUUACUUACAUGUAAUAAAAUGCACAGACUUAAGUGUAUACUUUGAUGAGUUCUGAUGAAUGUCUACAUGUGUGUAAUCACCACUGCAAUCAAGAUGGAAGGAAAGGCUGGGCGCGGUGGCUCACACCUGUAAUCCCAGCACUUUGGGAGGCCAAGGUGGGUGGAUCAUGAGGUCAGGAGUUCGAGACCAGCCUGACCAACAUGAUGAAACCCCGUCUCUACUAAAAAUAAAAAAAUUAGCCAGGCGUGGUGGCAGGCACCUGUACUCCCAGCUACUCAGGAGGCUGAGGCAGGAGAAUUGCUUGAACCCAGGAGGCGGAGGUUGCAGUGAGCCAAGAUUGCGCCAUUGCACUCCAGCCUGGGCGACAGAGCAAGACUCCAUCUCAAAAAAAAAAAAAAAAAAGAUGGAAAGACAGAUUUCUAUUGGUGAUUCUUAAAAGUAAUUUAUUUAUUUAUGUAUUUAUUUAUUUAUUUGAGAUGUAGUCUUGCUCUGUCAUCCAGACUGGAGUGCAAUGGUGUGGUCUCAGCUCACUGUAACUUCCGCCUCCUGGGUUCAAGCGAUUCUCCUGCCUCAGCCUCUGGAGUAGCUGGGAUUACAGGCGCUGGCCACCACGCCCGGCUAAUUUUUGUAUUUGUAGUAGAGACUGGGUUUCAGCAUGUUGGCCAGGCAGGUCUCGAACUCCUGACCUUGUGAUCCGCCCGCCUCAGCCUCCCAAAGUGCUGGGGUUACAAGUGUGAGCCACUGCGCCUGGCUCUUAAAAGUAAUUUCUUUCUGCUUAUAAAAUUCAUGUUCACUGUAGAACACUGGGGAUUGAGUAGAGAGGUCCGGCCACGAUGCAGGGAAACACUGUCUCAAGCGCCCCACCGCCCCACAUGGUCCCCAGAGACAGGGCCCCUAAGCGCUCACGUACAAGUAAAGGCGCUGACUGAGUGCGUCAUCUGCACGCAUACAAGCACUGCUAGCAUUCUGGCAUAUGUUUCUUUCAGCUUUUUUCUGUGCAGAUAUAUAUUACAUUUUUUUCUGUGUAUAUUUAUAUAUAUAUGAAACCAGAUCAGUUACACAAUUUAGUAUUUUUUUAACCUUAAUGUAGUAUAAGCAUUUCCCCCAUUGUACUUUGUAAAUAUGAUUUUUAAGAAGUCAUUGGUGUCUACUUUGUGAUAUUUGACUCAACCAGCCUUGAUAACAAAGAGUAGUUAGAGACAACUGAAUUUUUAAAAUGUAAAUCUGCUUUAUUUUUGGAAUAAAUAAUACAUUUACAUGGCUGGAAAUUCAAAGGAUACAAAAAGGCAUAUACUCCAGGCAACCACUAUGACCAGCUGCUGAUCACAAGUAGAGAACUUGUUUCUUUUCACCCCUCUUGCUCCUCCCCGGAGUUAUGAAAAAUUUCAAACCUGCCAAAAGUUUGAAGUUUACAACAAAUACCCUCCAACGUUUGGGUUGUCUCCCUCCCCCUUCUCUCCCUUUCUCCCUCUGAUUUCUUACAGAACCACGCUUUCAUGACCAUGCCCGGGAACUUCACGCUGGCGCGGUGAGGUCCUGCGCCUCCGCUUCCUGCACACACGUGCUUCUUAAUAGCUGCAGGCUAUUUCAUGAGAGGAAUUUGCUCACGUUAACAUGGCUGUUCCCAAAUGCCAGGCUGUUUUAAGUGUUUCCUAAUUAUAAACAGGCUGUGCUGUUUCCCUUGACCUAGGACUUGUUCUUGAGGACAGAAGUGGAGGUGGCGAGAUGCAAGGCCUACGUACGGACCGGCUUCCCCAGUAGGGCGGCGCCAAUGGGGGGCUCCCAAGCUGCUCCCAUCUCACCUCUGCUUCCGGGGUGCUGGGGGUUUGGGCCAGUGUUCCUUCUGCUUUUGUGAAGGGCCCUUACACUCGACUCGAAGUGCUCCUCCUAUUGGUUUUUAAUAAAUAUAUUUAUGGAAA